AGACCUGCAGAGUGAAGAAAGCUGGUAAUAGAUGUCUGACAAACUAAAGAAAGACUUGUGUUACGUGAGUAAGCCCUUUUCACUAAACUAAUGUAGUGAAAUGUUAUCCCGAAUUGAUUUCUGACACUGAAUGAUAUGUCGUUAUUAAUGAGUCAUCAGUUUGUAUGGUAAAUGCCAAUUGCUGAGUAACAGGUCUGAGGAACCUUCUAAUUGUGCCAGGUGAAAUGAUUUUUCUGCGAUACAGAUACAAAUUCAAUUAAAUUUUUUUUCCCCAUUACCUGUUGAGUUGGAAAUUUGGUGCAGGGCCUGCCUUUUAUUUUCCUCAGGGACAGAAUGGAAUACAGAAAUAUUGCUAGUUCUUAAGGCCAAAGAAGUUCUUAAGGCCAACUUAAUUGAUGAGAUUUUUUUCAGUUUUUAAAUGAACCUUUGUGGGAAACCACAAAAUAAAUGGGAGUGAAGGGAGAGUAGGGAUCACCAAACUCUUCAAAGGUUAAAACAUUUCUACUUCUUCUCUCAUCAGCACAAUUCAGACAGCCCGGAAUAUCAAGAUUCAUCUUUUUCACUAAUUGUGGCAUUCACAGAUGCAAAGUAUUGUUCCUGGGUGUGUCUGUGAGAGUAUUGCCAAAGGAGAGCAGUGAACUGGGAAAAGCAGACCCACCUCAAUGUGGGUGGGCAACAUCCAAUCGGCUGCCAGCUAGAAUAAACCAGGCAGGAGAAGAUGGAAGAGCCGACUUGCUGAAUCUUCCAGCCUUCAUCUUUCUCGUGUGCUGGAUGCUUCCUGCCCUCAAACAUCAGACUCCAGGUUCUUCGUCUUUUGGACUCUCGGAUUUACAUCAGUGGUUUACCAGGUGCUCUCAGGCCUUCAGCCACACACUGAAGGCUGAAUUGUCGGCUUCCCGACUUUUGAGAUUUUGAAACUUGGACUGAGCUACUGCUGGCUUCCUUGCUUCUCAACUUACAGAUGGGACUUCACCUAUAGAUCAUUACUUAUAACUUUAGUGGUGCAACAAAGCAACUUCCAAACACUGCUCCAGCAUCCCCACCUUCCCCGCAAGAGGCAAGGAACAGCUUCAAGUCUUCCUUUCUUGUUCACUCCUAUGACUCUGGAGGAGACAGCCCAACCAAGAGCCAUGGAAGGAUGUGGAGGAUGCGGAGGAUGCCCUGACUGCGCGGACCAGUAACGGCUGGGGCAACCCGAUUUCCCCACGCCCCCGCACCACGCUCUCCCUUGGCUCCAUCCUGCCGCACAGGCUCGAGCCCAGCGCGGCUGGAUCAACUUGUCAGUGUCGCUGUGGGGAAGAACAGGCAGCAGGGUUCCCCUUCCACAAAGCUCUGAGCUACAGGGGAAAGCUCUGAGUCGCCCUCUGGUGGAGGGAAUUUCAACCAUCCAAACUGCUUUCUGUGGAUCCAAUCUGUAAUCUGCAGAGCGCGUCUGGAUUGUAAUACAGAUUGCAAUAUGCAAGCCACACAAGUUAGGUAAAGAACAAGUGCGGGAUGCUGACAAUGGGCCAGUCGAGUGCAAAGCACUAUAUAUUCGUUUCUUAGACGCAGCUUCCGUGUAUAGAUUUUUAUUGUUCUAAAUAAUCUAGAAUCAUAUUGCCACUUCCCUCAGAGAUUGGGAAUAGAGUAAGAAUAGGCAAUUCUUAUACAGUGACAUACAGUGAUCCUAAAUUAUCAACUUGUCAAACAUUUAAUAAUUUCCUUCUGUUUUUUCGUCUGAAGAGACCGAAUGCUUAGAUAGAUAACAAUAGAUGCUUGGAAAAUGUAGCCAAGUAGUUCCUCUUGACAAAAUCUUCCCUUUUUGAUAGUUUGGAACAGAGCCACUGUAUGGUGACUGGUAGACUCCAAGAGUUGCUUUAAUUGAUACACUGAGACUGGGAUGGACAGAGUACAUUUGAUUGUCUAUUUUACCUGCAAUGCAAUAUAAAUCAACGUCAUUUGGCUUAAUGUUUUAAAUUCAUUACAUCAGUUAUAUUGAUAUUCUGUAAUAAACCAGCAUUUUUCCCCAUGACAUUAAUUUUUUUUAGUAUUUCUAUGUUUCAAAUAAAUACCUUUACUUAGUAAUUUGAAGUUGUUUACAAUGCUGUUUAAUUCAAGUGAACACGUACUUACAUCUGCUGAAUGAUCCGCCAUAGUCAACCUUGACACAAAAAACAAAAACCAAAACAAACUACUUUGAUGCAGCUACUAUCUUUUUAAAAAUAAAAAGCAGAAAAUUAGAUUAUAAGAAAACGAAAAAUGCAAGGAUCCUAAUGGAAAUUCUACUGGGCAAUAGAUAAUAUAUUUCUAGUCUACUACCAGCUAAUGGAGAAUUGCUGUAUAUACUACUUUCAUAUCACAUACAUAGUCCAAACUGAGCUUCUGAUAUCCCACACCCAAAGACAUGAACAUAUAUACGUGUGUGUGUGUGUGUAUAUGUGUGUGUGUAGGUAUACAGAUAGAUAAAUCAAUACAGUUAUAUACAUCUACAUGUGUCUAUAUAUAUAUGUCUCUUCCUGGAUAUAAAGAUAUCUAUAGGCAUAUACACACAUACAUAUACACACAUACAUUUAUAUAUGUAAAGUUCUCUCUAUGUAUAAAUCUGUUUGUAUACACAUAUAUGUGUGUGUGUCUGCCUAUAGACAUAUAUACAUCUACACAGAGAGAGAUACAGAUGUCUAUAGGCAUAUAUACAUAUACAUAUGUUUGUAUACAAAGAGAAAGAGAACUUUUAAGGAAUUGGCUCACAUUACAGUGGGGGGCUACAAUAAAAAAUCUGAAGUCCUAGGUAUGGCCCAAAAGACACUACAUAAUCUGACCAUGGCUAGUUCUCUGGCAUUCUCUCCUGGCUUAUUCUGCAUCAGCCACAUCCAUCAGCUUGAUAAGGAUGCUCUCUCCUCAGCAUCUUUGCACUUGCUGUUACUUUUGCCUGCAGUGCUCUUUAUAGAGUUCCCUUCAGUGAAGUCUUCCCUGAUCAUUCUAUAUCCCCUGUCUGUCAGUGCCUAUCCAUUUAACCUGUUUUAUUUUUCUUCAUUGCAUUAAUUACCUCCUGAAUUUAUGUUAUUUAUUUUUUUAACAUCUGCCUUCUCUAUCAGAUUGUAGCCUUCACCACAACAGUAGCUUUGUUUUCUUCAUUGCUACAUCUCUAGCACCUUGAACAGGAACUGAAUCUUUAGGCUCUCAAUAAAAAUUGGUCGAAUAAAUAAAUGAGUUCUCUUUAACUUUCUAAUAAUGUUGUAUACAACUGUAAGCUUCUUGAGAGCAGAAACUAUAUUUUAAUUGUUAUAUAUAUGUAUAUAUACAUAUGAGGGGCUCAAUAAAUAUUUUUGACUUAAUCACAUAAAAGGAAAUGCUGGGUAAGCUUAUAUAUUUCACUUUUUCUAACACUGGGUAUAUUUGAAGAUAGAAGGUGUUCAGUGGAUGUUUGUCAAAUACAUAAGUGGCUGAAUGAACAAAUAAAUACAAAGAUAAAGUAAAAUAUUUUCAAGUAGUAGGUACUCAGUGAAUGUUGGCUGCAUUAAUGAAUGAUCAAGUAAAUGAAAAUUUAAAGUUGAGCUUCAAAUGCAAACUCUUUUGGAACUGCAAAACAGUAAAGGUUGAUAGGGAUAAGGUUAAUAGGGAUAAAGGUUAACAGAUAGCUAAUUUAGUUUCAUUUAGUGUAUAGAGAAAUUAACUGCCUGUAACAACAACAGAAAUUUCAUAGAGUAAUGAAUUUAAAGAUUGGCAAAAGUAGAGUAUAUAUAGUCAAACAUAAUCCAAGAUUAUUGCUCUUCUAAGAGACGUUUUUAAUAAAAUGUCUGAAUUGUAUACAUUAUGUUUUUUAGAUCAUGUUCCCAAUGGCUUAGACAGCUAUAUUCAGAAAUACUAAAACAAUUUAGGUGUAAAAAGUCUAAUUGCCAGGAAUCAACAAGUGCAUGUCCUAAUGUUAUUUUCUUGAACAUCUAUUUCUGGAAUGGCCAAGGUUAGUUGGUGCACCAGAAUUUUUAAGUUCUUUUAUAACUUUUUAAAAGUUAAAUUUAGGCCGGGCGCGGUGGCUCACGCCUGUAAUCCCAGCACUUUGGGAGGCCGAGGGGGGCGGAUCACGAGGUCAGGAGAUCGAGACCAUCCCGGCUAAAACGGUGAAACCCUGUCUCUACUAAAAAUACAAAAAAUUAGCCGGGCGUAGUGGCGGGCGCCUGUAGUCCCAGCUACUUGGGAGGCUGAGGCAGGAGAAUGGCGUGAACCCGGGAGGCGGAGCUUGCAGUGAGCCGAGAUCCCGCCACUGCACUCCAGCCUGGGCGACAGAGCGAGACUCCGUCUCAAAAAAAAAAAAAAGUUAAAUUUAGCUUUCUGUUUUAUUUUUAUGUGUGUUUUCUGCUAUUUAUUUUUGCUUUUCUUUCUAUGUGGGGGUAAUGGAUAGAUGAAUUUUAUGGAGUGCAGCAGAAAAAUACAGAGUGAUUACAUUAUACCUCAUUUCCUUCACUAUUUUUAUACUUUAAAAAUUUAUUUGUAUUUUUACUCCCAAAUUUGCACCAGGAAAUACUGGAAAUAUUCACGUUUUGAUACAUACAUUCUGAGGGGAGCUAAUUUUGAAAAGUUACUGCAGAUUAGAAAAACAUGAUUAUGAAAGAACUGGAUUAACUUUCAUAAACUCUUACUUCUAAUUUGAAUAUCUGACUCUUGGCUGUGUAAUUUAGGAAAGUUAGUGCAUAUUAGAGUGGAGUGGAUCCUUGGAAUUAUCUCAAACCAGCUUUUUCCCUUUAUAGAUGAGGAGUUGAUGCCAAGAUAUUGUGUACAGAGCAUACAUAAAAAUAUUUAGGCCGGGCAUGGUGGCUCAUGCCUGUAAAUCACAGCACUCUGGGAGUCUGAGGCAGGGUAUCACCUGAGGUCAGGAGUUCGAGACCAGCCUGCCCAACAUGGUGAAACCCCCUCUAUAUAAAGAUACAAAAUAUUAACCGGGCGUGGUGGUGGGCGCAUGUAAUCCCAACUACUUGGGAGGCUGGGGCAGGAGAAUCGCUUGAACCUGGGAGGCAGAGGUUGCAGUGAGUCGAGAUUGUGCCAUUGCACUCCAGCCUGGGCAACAAGAAGGAAACUCCGUCUCAAAAAAAAAAAAAGGCAAAGAAUAAAAUGCAGGUUUCUUGAUUUCUAGGCCUUUGCCCUUUCCACACAUCAUUUUAAAUUUUAAUUAUAUAUACACACACAAAUACACAUACAUAUAUAUGCAAUUAUUCAUGUAAUCAUCUAUAUGUACAUAGUCACACAAAUUUAAAGUAAUAUCCAUGUCUAAUAUCUAUGUAUCUCUAUAUAAUAUAUUACAGUCUUUAAAAAAAAUAAGUGCAAGCUCCUUGAGAGCAGAUAUUGUAGCAUAUGCUUAAAUUUCUUCUCCUCAAAACGUCAUUCUGGGCUCUGUGCACAGACAGGUGCCUUAUGAAAUAUGUUAAACAGAAUUCAAUUAGACAAAGAAUUACACAACAACCGCCGUGGAUCCGGGCCGGGCUUUGGCCCUUUCCCUGCUCAGGAGAAGCGCGGGUGAGUGAGUCCGCUCCGGCUCCUCGCCGGGGUUUAGGGGCGCCGCGGAGCCGGUUCCCUGGGAGGCUGCGGCGGCUGUAGCUGAGGUUUCACCCCUUUGGGUUUUCCAGCCAGCAAGUACUUCUGAGAGCGUGGCGGGGUCUCCGGCCACAAGCUCAGUUCCGGUCAGCCAGGCAGCGGAACUGAGGAGGCAGAUUGGCGGGGGCGGGAGGUGGCGUAGAACGAACAAGGGACUUGGGCCGACGACCUUUUCGUCCCUGGAGGUCAGAGUGUAAUCAGAAGCCCUGCGCUGCGGCGCCUGUUGCCGGGCAACCUGCAGACGCGGGCCUGGACUGUCUAGACUGUCCUGUCUAAAGCUUUCUGAAUGCGGUUUUUGGAGGAAUCGCGCUAGUUUAUACCUUUUCCAACUCUUCUAACUCUGGACCUCUUCUUACCGAGCUUGUUAGGUGAAAUCAGGCUGACUGUCUCUUGUGCCCCUCGCCUGUCCUGUCCAGGAAUCCCAGUUAGGUAGGGGAUGGGGAAUUCCUUCUGCUACACUGCAGUAUACUGCAUGAUAAACACAGGAACUCAAAUGGAUUUAGAGGUUAAAGGAGUUGCUGCCACUUCUAGGAGCCAAAUUCAGCCAUUCUUUGGAAGAAAGAAGCCUCUACAACAAAGGUGGACUUCUGAGUCAUGGACAAACCAGAAUUCUUGCCCACCAGUGGUCCCACGACUUGAUUUGGGAAGCCUUGUUGACUCUGAUGAUGAGGACAAUUUUUCAUAUAUUCCACUUAGUACAGCAAACCUGCCAAAUUCAUCUUCUACUCUUGGCUGGGUCACACCAUGUCAAACUCCAUAUACUCAGUAUCAUCUAAAUAAAUUGGAUCAGAACAUAAUACCUGAAAAUUUGCCAGCACCAACAGACAAAUGUAAACUAAAAUAUCAGCAAUGUAAAACUGAAAUUAAAGAGGGCUAUAAGCAGUAUAGUCAGAGAAAUGCAGAAAAUACAAAAUCAAAUGUUACACAUAAACAGUCUCCAAGAAACAAGAUAGAUGAAAAGUGUGUGCAAGAUGAAGAAGCCAACACAGAUGACCUUACGACUCUGGAUAGGAAAGCCAUCUUACAGCAAGGUUAUGCAGACAACUCUUGCGAUAAACAACAGAGGGCAAGAAAAUUGGAUGCAGAAAUUGUGGCUGCAGAGAAGAAGAAACAGAUUGUUGCAGAGCAAGUGAUGAUAGACCACUUAUCUAGGGCUGUCAUCAGUGAUCCAGAGCAAAAUUUAGCCAUUGAGCAAAAAGAAAGUGAUCAUAUCCUUCCAGAUUCAAAGAUGACACCUCUUCGAUUUAGAAAAAGAACACUACAUGAAACAAAGAUAAGAACUCAUUCUACAUUAACUGAAAAUGUGCUUUCUCAUAAAUUACAGUUUGAUGGUAGGAUCGUAUCACGUAAUGGACGUGAUGCUUGCAGAGAGCUCAUUGGGUUCUUUUUCACUCAUGACCAAUCCCUUACAAUUUAUGAAUAUCGACAAUUUGGGAAAAAUAGAACAAAUGUGCUUCCUUUUAUUCAAAAAAGCAUUUAUAGUCAUCAGUGUGGACGAAGAAAAGGAAAACAAUACCGACUUGGUGAUUUUUAUGUUGGUGCAACCUUGACAUUUUUGAGUUCUGAUCAUCUCAGCCUUCCAGAAAGCAUCAAAGAAAACACAUUACUUAAACUCCGAAUCACAAAUAUUGAUCAAAUAGCUUUGGAUUCUCUCAAAACUGCUUCUAUGGAACAGGAGGAUGAUAUAAUCAUUCAAGAAACCAAUGAUAGGCUGGUCUUCAAAGCAAUUCAAGAUGUGCUAAAAGAAAAACUACAUAAAAGAGGUGUUCGUAUUUUGACUGGAUUGGGAAAAUAUUUUCAACAGUUGGACAAGGAAGGAAAUGGACUUUUAGAUAAGGCAGAUUUUAAGCAAGCUCUAAAAGUGUUUCACUUAGAAGUGUCUGAAAAGGAUUUUGAGUCUGCAUGGCUAAUUCUGAAUGACAAUGGCAAUGGCAAGGUUGAUUAUGGAGAAUUCAAACGUGGUAUUAUUGGUGAAAUGAAUGAAUACAGGAAAUCAUAUGUUCGAAAGGCCUUUAUGAAACUGGAUUUCAACAAAAGUGGCAGUGUGCCUAUUAUAAACAUAAGAAAAUGUUACUGUGCAAAGAAGCAUUCUCAAGUAAUUUCAGGCCAUUCAACAGAGGAAGAAAUCAAAUCAUCCUUUCUAGAAACAUUAAAAGUUGCCUGCAGCAAGUCUGAUGAAGUGUCAUAUGGUGAAUUUGAAGAUUACUAUGAAGGUUUAAGUAUAGGAAUAGUAGAUGAUGAAGACUUUGUUAACAUCUUACGUACUCCAUGGGGGAUUUAGUCUUUAAUAAUACAUAUGUCAUCAACACUAAGCAUUUUAUUGGAGAGAUGAUAUCAAUGUAAAGGAUGAUCAAACACUGGAAUAUAUUUUCCUAGGACUUCCUUUAUUCUGGUUUCUUGUUUGUUUGUUUUGUUUUGUUUUGUUUUCUCAAAAAUGUUGAAUUUGGAAAGAGAACUAUCCAGAAAGAUAGAUGUAGGGGUGUGUUAGUGUUUGUGCAUGUGUAUGCCUGUUCACAUGUCCUUACAUUUGUAAAGAUAUCUUUUUGGUUUAUUACUUAUCUUGCGUAUAUUUUAGAGGUCAUUUUUUAUUAACUUCAGUAGGAAAGUUACAUCUGCAUCAAACAAUAUGGCAACAUCUAUUUAUUAACCAAGUUUCCUGUCCUUUCACAUUGUUUUUUGCUACCUCUUCCUCAGAAUAUAUUUGCCACCAUGGUCAAUUUGAUAAAUUAGAAUUGGGCCCAAAGCCAGUGAGAUAAUUCAAUGUGUUUUUAACACAUGAAAAUAUUAAAGGAUAUGCAAGAGAAAUUUUUCAAGCAGUGUGAUUAUAGAUGUUUUCUGUAUAUAGAAUAUUUCAAAUGAUGGAGGUUUACCCCAUGAUGCUCAUUUAAAUACUGACUUGUCUUUUAAAUCUGUCUUCUAAAUUAUGUACUGUUGUUGGUUAAAUAGAGCACAAUGUAGUUAUUCUAAUGCCCAGUUGUAUUUGUUCUUUUAUUCUGCUUUUUAACUGUAAUCCUUUUUACCAGCAUACGAUUGUUAUUGAGCAAUAUGAAAGGGAAAUGUUCUUUAUUAAAAUCAAUACAUUAUCUUAUUAAACAAAGAUCCUAAAAGUAUAUUGUUGCAUAUAUGAAUCCAAGGAAUAGUUCAGUAAUUAUUGCCUAAAAUGUGAAAGCAUAUUUUGUAUCCUAAAAUGAAUGUAUGAUAUUCUAAACAUCUGUUUUAGUAUAACAAACAAUUGAAACAUUUCCUUCUAAAUAUAUGUUAUUUAAUAGUUACAUGUAUUAUAAUCAUUCUUUCUAAAUUCUUUGCUAGUCAUUUCUUCCUGGGAAUACAGAGAAAAGAGACAACUUUAUGAGUUGUUUUCAACUUCAUAAUUUUAAAUUUUCUAUGUUAAUAUAACAUAAAUUAGAAAAAAUAAGUGAUUCAAAAUGAAAAUAUUUACUUUGUAGAAUAUGACUUUAGACAUAUCACUGUAUCCAUCUAUACUUGGCAGCAACAUGAGAAGUGUGAUACAUGUGAACCCAACAAAUUCAAAGUUGCACUUUUCAAGAUGUGAGAAGGUACUAAAACUUAAUACUAAAACAUGAGAGGGAAAAUAUGUGUAAACCUCUAGUGCUAUUUUCACUGGCUAAAUUCUUUAUUUCUUGAUUUUUUUAAAAAUUAGGUUAUUAAAAUUAAAACAAUAUGCUAGAAGACAUUUUGGCAGAAAUAAGUCUAUAACACUAUUUUUGUCACAUAUCUUUUUCUUGGAAAAAUUUAUCCAACUAUAGACAUCUUAAACCCUACAAAUUGUUCUUGUUAAAAAUGACUAAUACUGGGGGUGCUCAAUAUGCAUAUAGUGUUUUUCAUUGAUAAUUUUUAUUUAGUUCUUAAGAAACCUGUUCUUAAUGUUGGCAUGUCACAUUUUUCUGUUACUAUAAUCAGAAAAUGUAUAGUCUGUUAUACUGUAAAAAAAAAAAAAAAGGGAAGCUACUUUUGGAAUGUAACGUGUUAACAUGACAGCAUACUCUUAGUAUUAAUCUUAAUCUUCCUAACAUAAGCAUUCACAUGUGGUUAUUUGUAGGAAAUAGCUCUAUUUAUGAGAUUUUUUUUGGUGUAUUUUGUUAGAAUUGGUGACACAGUAAAUCAUUCUGCUUUUGGAUUUGCCUGACUGCCUGCAUUCUUCUUUGAUUUUGGUAUAGUAAAAUCUGUUAUUUAGUGUUAAACUUAAUAAAAGAGCAUUUAAGAGAAGUGACAUUUCAAACAUCCACAACACAACUGACUUUUGAAAUCCUAUGCUUAAUAGUCUUUGUAAUUCUAAAAGACCUUUUGAAAAUGUUAAAAUAUUAAAUUAUAUGUUGUAAUGCUGUUACAUGAAUUUUAUAGUUAUGUAUAUUUUAUAGAUCUCUAUGUCUUUGUAAGUUACUUGCUUGUAUGCUAUAUAAUUGCUUUCUCAGUUAACCAUACUGUUUAUGGAAUUGUAUAUACUGAUUUUUCUGUUUUUAUAUUUUAAAAAUAAAAGUUGAGAAUUUUAAGGAAAAACAUUUUAUUAAAAAGACAAGGUAUAUUAUAUAGGAAUUUUAAGCUAACUUUUAAUGGAAAGGACAUACAUAUUUGCAUGAUGGAGCAAUCACAUUAUAGUUAAACAUGUAUGUCCCUGUUUUAAAUUUUAUAGUAUAUAAAUAUAUGUGCUAAUGAACCAGCGACUCUGCAUAGAGGCAGUCACUUAGAGUAAUUAAUAAUCUUGAUACAGCUGUAGAUCAUAUCUUAUUUUACAUAUUACUUUUGACUUCCAGUUUAAGUUGUUUGUUAUCAAGUAUUUCAGGAGAGAAUUGUGUACAUUAGGCUAUGUUUACUGCAGAUUAUGUAACAUGCUUUUAUGAGAUUAUAGUUUGUAGUGCUUGCAAAUAUAAAACAUGUACCCUGAUAAACUAUAAUCACUACUAGGUUGACCAGCAAGGACAAACAUGAAAAUGCUUAAAAAAAAGAAAGCGCUUAAAACAAAGAAAUAGAAGGUAAUGGGCAUAUAUAAAAUAAGCCAAGCAAGAGAAGAGCAAAGACAAUCUGCAGGGUGGACAUGGAUGUAUUCGUUUCUGAUCAUGAGAAGAGGCUCUUGUCAUACAUAUCGUUCCAUUUUUAUUUUAAAGUUCUAUAAACUUCUGAGGUAAACUGAUUUCUUGGAUGUACUUAAUAAAGAAUAAAUGUUUCAUAUUGGA